ACUGCGAGUUUCCGGUCUGGGCUUUGGCGGGUCUGGUUUGAAGCUCUCCUGUUUGACGAAAGUAUGUCUCAGGAAGGUGCGGUCCCAGCUAGCGCGGUUCCCCUGGAAGAAUUAAGUAGCUGGCCAGAGGAGCUAUGCCGCCGGGAACUGCCGUCCGUCCUGCCCCGACUCCUCUCAUUGUCUCAACAUUCUGACAGUUGGAUUGAGCAUAUUCAAAUUUUGAAAAUUAUUGUAGAAAUGUUUUUACCUCAUAUGAACCACCUGACAUUGGAACAGACUUUCUUUUCACAAGUGUUACCAAAGACUGUGAAAUUAUUCGAUGACAUGAUGUAUGAAUUAACCAGUCAAGCCAGAGGACUGUCAAGCCAAAAUUUGGAAAUCCAGACCACUCUAAGGAAUAUUUUACAAACAAUGGUGCAGCUCUUAGGAGCUCUCACAGGAUGUGUUCAGCAUAUCUGUGCCACACAGGAAUCCAUCAUUUUGGAAAAUAUUCAGAGUCUCCCCUCCUCAGUCCUUCAUAUAAUUAAAAGCACAUUUGUGCAUUGUAAGAAUAGUGAAUCUGUGUAUUCUGGGUGUUUACACCUAGUUUCAGACCUUCUCCAGGCUCUUUUCAAGGAGGCCUAUUCUCUUCAAAAGCAGUUAAUGGAACUGCUGGACAUGGUUUGCAUGGACCCUUUAGUAGAUGACAAUGAUGAUAUUUUGAAUAUGGUAAUAGUUAUUCAUUCUUUAUUGGAUAUCUGCUCUGUUAUUUCCAGUAUGGACCAUGCAUUUCAUGCCAAUACUUGGAAGUUUAUAAUUAAGCAGAGCCUUAAGCACCAGUCCAUAAUAAAAAGCCAGUUGAAACACAAAGAUAUAAUUACUAGCUUGUGUGAAGACAUUCUUUUCUCCUUCCAUUCUUGUUUACAGUUAGCUGAGCAGAUGACACAGUCAGAUGCACAGGAUAAUGCUGACUACAGAUUAUUUCAGAAAACACUCAAAUUGUGUCGUUUUUUUGCCAACUCCCUUUUGCACUACGCUAAGGAAUUUCUUCCUUUCCUCUCUGAUUCUUGCUGUACUUUGCACCAACUGUAUCUUCAGAUACACAGCAAGUUUCCUCCAAGCCUUUAUGCUACCAGGAUUUCUAAAGCACACCAAGAGGAAAUAGCAGGUGCUUUCCUAGUGACACUGGAUCCACUUAUCAGUCAGCUGCUCACAUUUCAGCCUUUCAUGCAGGUGGUUUUGGACAGUAAAUUAGACCUGCCAUGUGAACUGCAGUUUCCACAAUGUCUUCUUCUGGUUGUUGUCAUGGAUAAGCUGCCAUCUCAGCCUAAGGAAGUGCAAACCCUGUGGUGCACAGACAGCCAGGUCUCAGAAACGACAACCAGGAUAUCUCUACUCAAAGCCGUUUUCUACAGUUUUGAGCAGUGUUCUGGUGAACUCUCUCUACCUGUUCAUUUACAGGGAUUAAAGAGUAAGGGGAAAGCUGAGGUGGCUGUCACCUUGUAUCAGCAUGUUUGUGUUCAUCUGUGUACAUUUAUUACUUCCUUUCAUCCCUCACUGUUUGCUGAACUGGAUGCUGCUCUGCUGAAUGCUGUACUUAGUGCUAAUAUGAUCACCUCUUUGUUAGCUAUGGAUGCAUGGUGCUUCCUUGCUCGAUAUGGGACUGCUGAACUGUGUGCACACCAUGUCACCAUAGUGGCUCAUCUGAUAAAGUCAUGCCCUGGAGAAUGUUAUCAACUCAUCAACCUAUCAAUACUGUUGAAGCGUCUCUUUUUCUUCAUGGCACCACCCCAUCAGCUGGAGUUUAUCCAGAAAUUUUCCCCAAAAGAAGCAGAAAAUCUGCCUCUGUGGCAACAUAUUUCCUUCCAGGCGUUACCUCCUGAGCUUAGGGAACAAACUGUCCAUGAGGUCACCACAGUAGGCACUGCAGAAUGCAGGAAAUGGCUGAGCAGGAGUCGUACUUUGGGAGAACUAGAAUCUCUGAACACAGUACUGUCUGCUUUGCUUGCAGUAUGUAAUUCUGCUGGUGAAGCUUUGGAUACAGGAAAACAAACUGCAAUUAUCGAAGUUGUGAGUCAGCUUUGGGCUUUUUUAAACAUUAAACAGGUAGCAGAUCAACCUUAUGUUCAACAGACAUUCAGCCUUUUACUUCCACUGUUGGGAUUUUUCAUUCAAACUCUAGAUCCUAAACUGAUACUUCAGGCAGUAACUUUGCAGACCUCGCUACUUAAAUUAGAGCUUCCUGACUAUGUUCGUUUGGCAAUGUUGGAUUUUGUAUCUUCUUUAGGAAAACUUUUUAUACCUGAAGCUAUCCAGGACAGAAUUCUGCCCAACCUGUCCUGUAUGUUUGCCUUACUGCUAGCUGACAGGAGUUGGCUGCUAGAACAACAUACCUUGGAGGCGUUUACUCAGUUCGCUGAGGGAACAAAUCAUGAAGAGAUAGUUCCACAGUGUCUCAGUUCUGAAGAAACUAAGAACAAAGUUGUAUCCUUUCUGGAGAAGACUGGGUUUGUAGAUGAAACUGAAGCUGCCAAAGUGGAACGUGUGAAACAGGAAAAAGGUAUUUUCUGGGAACCCUUUGCUAAUGUGACUGUAGAAGAAGCAAAGAGGUCAUCUUUACAGGUAUGGGCUGAUUUCAAUAGGGGCCAAACUUUAACAAGGCAAAUUCUGCCCUUUUUACUUACUGACGAAACAAACCAGUGUGGUUUCCAGCCUUAUGCUGAAUUUCAAAUCAAAUAGAUCUAGACAUGUAAAAUUCUGUUUUAUGGUAGUUGCUUUUAAAAUUAAGAAGUGGGACUACACCAUAUCAAAUAUAUUCUUUCAGUAUGUUUGAAUUAUUGGUAGUAACCUUUAAGGGAAGUUACAUAUUGUACCAGUGAUGCUAUAAAUGCAGUCUUUACUGAACCACAGAAGAAAAUGAAAGAAACUUACUCCUAAAUGUUUAGUUUGAUUCCUUGCCUUAUUAAUCAAAUGAGUCUCCUAAUAAUUUUUGGCAGUAACUGAAGAUCACAUCUACUUAUUAAAAGGCAGAAUUUGACACCAAUAAGGAUAUUCAAAAUAUUGUUUUGAGCACUAUUAGUAUAGUAAUUAGUAUAGUAGUAAUUCAUGAAGAACAACAUUCUGAUAAGUUUUAGUCAAACUCUCAUAAAAAGAAAAUACAUUUAUGAACUUGUUUAUAAGACAUGUAAGCUUGGACUAUGCAGCACUUCUCAUUGGGAGCCCUUUGGGACAGGAUACUUGUUGUAUACCACAUACAAACUAAGACACUGGUAGUAGCACUCUGAAUUGCUAUGAUAAACCAAAAUGCCUUUACAUAUUUUUCUAGAUGACUGUGUAGGGGUUUUGGGGUGCAUCCUCCUACCCUUGUGAUCCAAUGACUAGAAUAAAAUUUGCAUGUAAGCUUUACUCCAGUCCAAAAGGAAGGUUCUUUAUAUUUAGAAUGGAUAUUGUGAUAUUACUUAUGUUUUUUUUCCAGCCUUAUGCAAAAAGAGCUCGUCAGGAGUUCCCCUGGGAAGAAGAGUACAGGUCAGCGCUGCAUACAAUAGCAGGGGCUUUGGAAGCAACUGAGUCACUACUCCAAAAGGGUCCUGCUCCAGCCUGGCUUUCAAUGGAAAUGGAGGCGCUCCAAGAAAGGAUGGAUAAGCUAAAACGUUACAUACAUACUCUAGGGUGAAACUUAUCACUAGGCAGAACUGGGUUUGAUGCUUUGUCAACUGAAAAUACUUAUGUCUGUACAUUUUCUAACAGAUAUAAAACAAAUUUUGUAAAGUUGAAUCUAGUGAAAAUAAUCUUUAUUUGACAUUUAGAGAACAGGAUUGUGGGGAAUAUUCUUAUUAAGAACUUUGGUACAAUGUACUACAUGUGGAACAGUCAGGAACUGCCUAGGUCCACAAAGAACCAUUUACUCAGAUAGUCUAACUGUAAACAAAUAAAUAAGCUGCCUAAGGAAACCUCAGCAAUUUAAAAUCAUUUAUAUAAUUUAUAGCUAAAAUUUUUUAAAGUUGUAUUUCAUAAUAGAGCUUACUCUUAUGUUAAAGAAUGGCACAAAAUUAAGCUAACCAGCUUGAAUUACAUUUUCUUUACUUCCAGAAUUGUCCUGGAAAAAGCAGUAAAUUCGACCUCUCCUCAGCUACUUGCUCUUCAUAGAAACUGGCCUCAGUCAAAUGCACAAAGGCUCUUCCUCCUGGAAACCAGUACUGUGAGCCUCACCACCCAGGGCUUUUAGCCAGCACUCACAGUCAGUCUCCUACUUCAGUUGGCACAGACUGGAUAAUGAGCUCCUGGGAUGGGAAAAGCAGGCCACUUUGGGGUUUUCUUGUCCCAAAGCCUGCUUUUGAGGUAUUGAUUUUUUUUAAAAAAAGGGAAUCCUUUUUCCUAAAGUUUAACUCACAUCUAUUGUCACCAGUUAUUAUCUUCCCAGUUCAGCUCCCCUUCUUCUUCCCAGCCUUCAGCCUCUCCCUGCAACAAAAUAAAGCACACCAAGAACCCACUGAAACAAAUCAUAUGCAAAAAUCAUACGCAAAUUUGAAAAAGCAGGAAUUUAAAAUUUAUCUUUUGAUGCCAGAAACACUACCUCGUACUAAGUAAAAUAACUUAGAGCUCUAACAGAAAGUUGAAAAGUAGGAUUACAAAACCAUGGCACUGGAAAAUAGCUUUUCAAAAACCAUAAAAUCCAGUAAAAAUCAGUGUGGAUGACACCAAAUCCUUAUUUUAAUCCCUUUUUUUUCUUUUUCAAAUAAAAAGGUUACAAUAGCUCAUUAAACAAA